GUGCCGGGAAGUGGCUCCAGGGAGAAGAGGCCUCUUCCCUCACCCGCUGUGGGAGCUGCGCCCCGAAAGCCUGCCCCGGCACGUCGGGCUCUCCUGACCCGCCAAGACCAGAGAGCCGUUGGCGCCCUCCGCCCGGGCCUGCCGGUCCGUUUAUUUUAAGAAGCUUUGUGCGCCUGCUGUGGGGAUUUCUGAUCCAGGCUGCGAAGAAUUUCGAAGUCUGGAAAAUAGCAACUGUGUUUGUUUCUAAAGGAUCUUCUCCUGACCCAGCAUCGCUCAUCACAAUGAAGAACCAAGACAAAAAGAACGGGGCUGCCAAACAAUCCAAUCCAAAAAGCAGCCCAGGACAACCGGAAGCAGGACCCGAGGGAGCCCAGGAGCGGCCCAGCCAGGCGGCUCCUGCAGUAGAAGCAGAAGGUCCCGGCAGCAGCCAGGCUCCUCGGAAGCCGGAGGGGGCUCAAGCCAGAACGGCUCAGUCUGGGGCCCUUCGUGAUGUCUCUGAGGAGCUGAGCCGCCAACUGGAAGACAUACUGAGCACAUACUGUGUGGACAAUAACCAGGGGGGCCCCGGCGAGGAUGGGGCACAGGGUGAGCCGGCUGAACCCGAAGAUGCAGAGAAGUCCCGGACCUAUGUGGCAAGGAAUGGGGAGCCUGAACCAACUCCAGUAGUCAAUGGAGAGAAGGAACCCUCCAAGGGGGAUCCAAACACAGAAGAGAUCCGGCAGAGUGACGAGGUCGGAGACCGAGACCAUCGAAGGCCACAGGAGAAGAAAAAAGCCAAGGGUUUGGGUGAGCAGAGGGCGGCUCUUUGUGAAGCUGGUGAGGAGAGGGAGUUUGGACUUGACGUUCUCUGGGCCAGUCUGUUCUGCCAGGAUUCAAAGGAAAACGGGAAGGAGAUCACGUUGCUGAUGCAGACAUUGAAUACUCUGAGUACCCCAGAGGAGAAGCUGGCUGCUCUGUGCAAGAAGUAUGCUGAACUGCUGGAGGAGCACCGGAAUUCACAGAAGCAGAUGAAGCUCCUACAGAAAAAGCAGAGCCAGCUGGUGCAAGAGAAGGACCACCUGCGCGGUGAGCACAGCAAGGCCGUCCUGGCCCGCAGCAAGCUUGAGAGCCUAUGCCGUGAGCUGCAGCGGCACAACCGCUCCCUCAAGGAAGAAGGUGUGCAGCGGGCCCGGGAGGAGGAGGAGAAGCGCAAGGAGGUGACCUCGCACUUCCAGGUGACACUGAAUGACAUUCAGCUGCAGAUGGAACAGCACAAUGAGCGCAACUCCAAGCUGCGCCAAGAGAACAUGGAGCUGGCUGAGAGGCUCAAGAAGCUGAUUGAGCAGUAUGAGCUGCGCGAGGAGCAUAUCGACAAAGUCUUCAAACACAAGGACCUACAACAGCAGCUGGUGGAUGCCAAGCUCCAGCAGGCCCAGGAGAUGCUAAAGGAGGCAGAAGAGCGGCACCAGCGGGAGAAGGAUUUUCUCCUGAAAGAGGCAGUAGAGUCCCAGAGGAUGUGUGAGCUGAUGAAGCAGCAAGAGACCCACCUGAAGCAACAGCUUGCCCUAUACACAGAGAAGUUUGAGGAGUUCCAGAACACACUUUCCAAAAGCAGCGAGGUAUUCACCACAUUCAAGCAGGAGAUGGAAAAGAUGACUAAGAAGAUCAAGAAGCUGGAGAAAGAAACCACCAUGUACCGGUCCCGGUGGGAGAGCAGCAACAAGGCCCUGCUUGAGAUGGCUGAGGAGAAAACAGUCCGGGAUAAAGAACUGGAGGGCCUGCAGGUAAAAAUCCAACGGCUGGAGAAGCUGUGCCGGGCACUGCAGACAGAGCGCAAUGACCUGAACAAGAGGGUACAGGACCUGAGUGCUGGUGGCCAGGGCUCCCUCACUGACAGUGGCCCUGAGAGGAGGCCAGAGGGGCCUGGGGCUCAAGCACCCAGCUCCCCCAGGGUCACAGAAGCGCCUUGCUACCCAGGAGCACCGAGCACAGAAGCAUCAGGCCAGACUGGGCCUCAAGAGCCCACCUCCGCCAGGGCCUAGAGAGCCUGGUGUUGGGUCAUGCUGGGAAGGGAGCGGCAGCCCAGCCAGGCCUGGCCCAUAAAAGGCUCCCAUGCUGAGCAGCCCAUUGCUGAAGCCAGGAUGUUCUGACCUGGCUGGCAUCUGGCACUUGCAAUUUUGGAUUUUGUGGGUCAGUUUUACGUACAUAGGGCAUUUUGCAAGGCCUUGCAAAUGCAUUUAUACCUGUAAGUGUACAGUGGGCUUGCAUUGGGGAUGGGGGUGUGUACAGAUGAAGUCAGUGGCUUGUCUGUGAGCUGAAGAGUCUUGAGAGGGGCUGUCAUCUGUAGCUGCCAUCACAGUGAGUUGGCAGAAGUGACUUGAGCAUUUCUCUGUCUGAUUUGAGGCUCAGACCCCUCCCUGCCCUUCAGAGCUCAAGACAAGUAAUACACCCAGGUCUUGACUGCAUUUGUCUUGUGAGCAGGGCUUGCUUGGUCAGCUCAGGCCCUCCUAGCUGCUCUGGAGGCUCCUUUGAUUCUCUAGACCUGGAAAAGGUGUCCCUAGGCAGAGCCCUGGCAGGGCGCUCAGAGCUGGGGAUUUCCUGCCUGGAACAAGGGACCUGGAGAAUGUUUUUGCGUGGGAUGAUGUGCUGGUCAGGAGCCCCUUGGGCAUCGCUUCCCCUGCCCUUUGGUAGUGCCAGGACCAGGCCAAUGAUGCUUCUCAGUAGCCUUAUCAUUCACAGGUGCCUCUCUAGCCUGCACAAAUGAUUGACAAGAGAUCACCCAAAGGAUUAUUUCUGAAGGUGUUUUUUUCUUUAUUUCUUUUUCUUUUUUUUUUUUUUUCUUUUUCUUUUUUUUUUGCACAUGACAGUGUUUGUAUUGAGGACCUUCCAAGGAAGAGGGAUGCUGUAGCAGUGGUGCCUGGGUGCCUGGCCUCCAGUGUCCCACCUCCUUCACCACCCCACUUGGCUCCUUUGCCAUCUUGAUGCUGAGGUUUCCUGUUUGGUGAGAUCAGGUUGUUUGUGGUAAAAGAAAGGAAAGGGCUUCUGAUGGCUUUGCCACAAGCUUACCUGUGGGUUUCAGUCCUGAGAGGCCACCACCAGUUCCCAUCAGCACUGUCUCCAUGCAGCAGUUGCUGGGUCCCAUGUCCAGCUGCCUCUUUGGCUUCAUGGGUUUUUCUGCUUCCUGCCCCCACCCCCACAUGUGCAAUCCUCAAGAUUUGUCCUGAUUCUAUUUCCUGGCACCUCCCUGCCUGUCCUUGGGGAUUCUACUUCUUCCUGUGUGGGAGCCCAUAGCUGUUGUCUAACAGGUAAGAAAUGAAAUUGAACUAUUGACUGGGCCCCAGAAAUCCAUAAAAUGGCUGCAGACAGUUGUUUCUGUGUCCUGUUCUACCCCCACUCCAGUACAUAACUACUAUGUACUGUGUAGAGCCAUUCUAUAUGCUGAAUGUUCUGCUGUUGCAAACUUGCCAGGGUAUUAGCCAGUGUUUGUGCCAAGCAGUUUUCUGGGACAACAGAAUGACUCAGACCAAGAUGGAUAGGAUGGUUAGGGCUUUGCUUCUUGCUGUUUUUCUUUGAAGCUAGUUCAUUGUCCUGCAGGUCCCUUCAUCUUCCAUACCUAGCCCACUCUUUUAGCCCUUACCUUAAAUCUCUCAGAUAAGUUGGUUCACAAAGAAUGUUAAGUACUGAAUCAUGUGUGACUGAGACCAGAGAUGGCAAAUGAAUGGCACACCAUUUCUCCUUCUCCUGCCCCAGGGCAGGUACCACUGAUCUGCAUCAGAGUUGCCUGCUAUUCUCUGGUGUAUCCUUCACAUCUAGGUGCCCUCAAGCAGCUGUGUGAGUGUUGAGAUCUCUGCCAUCUCUGGCUGAGAUACUGCUGUCCUGUGAAGUGUUUCCCAUGACCUUUUUCUUCCCCUUUGAAUCCCUCUGUCUGGAGUAGUCCUUGCCUCUUCCUGCUCCAGUAGGGCCUUUUCCCUACCCCAGCCCCUGUGCCAGGCUAAGCUGGUACAAGAGCUGCCAACCUCACAGAGUGUUUGCUAGGCGAGAGAGGUGCAGGGAAGAGGCAGAGGUAUGCACCUUCCCCCUUGAAGAGAGGGGAAAGGCCUACAGUGGCCCACAUAAUUGCCUGACUCACACUUCAGCUACCUCUUAAUGCCUGUGGAGGGACUGGAGCUGCUGGAUCCCAGUGUGGUGGUGUAGGAGGCCACAGUGAGCAGGUGGCCCCAGCUGGGUUUCCCAGGUCAGGAAUGUGGGCCCCAGGCAAGGUGCAGCCUUUGCUCACAGCUCCAUCCAUGUCUAGACCUUCAGGCCAGUCUGCAGAUGAGGUUCCCUACCUUUUUCUUCUCUUCAUUGACCAAAUCAACCAAUCACUACAGCUGCUCUGCUUCUGCUUUCCAAAGUAGCCCAGGUCCUGGGCCAGAUGCAGGGGAGGUGCCUAUCCAUGAGUGAAGGCCAGUGUCUUCCUCACCUGGGUGGGUCCCACACUUGUGACCUCAGUUUUAGGACCAAGAUCUGUGUUGGUUUCUUAGAUUGCUAGCUUUUCCUCCAGGGGACCACAGCAGGUGAAGCUCAAGAGCGCAUGGCUCUGCUAAUAGUAAAUUGUUUUCAGGGCCUUGUCCAGCUGAGAGCUUCAUGUCCACCAGAUUCUGAGAGGUGUCAGCAGCACUUUUUUUUUUUAUUUGUUGUUUGUUUUCCAUGAGGUUAUCGGACCAUGGGCUGAGCUCAGGCACUUUCUGUAGGAGACUGUUAUUUCUGUAAAGAUGGUUAUUUAACCCUCCUCCACCCCAUCACGGUGGCCCUGAGGGCUGACCCGGAGGCCAGUGGAGCUGCCUGGUGUCCACGGGGGAGGGCCAAGGCCUGCUGAGCUGAUUCUCCAGCUGCUGCCCCAGCCUUUCCGCCUUGCACAGCACAGAGGUGGUCACCCCAGGGACAGCCAGGCACCUGCUCCUCUUGCCCUUCCUGGGGGAAGGGAGCUGCCUUCUGUCCCUGUAACUGCUUUCCUUAUGGCCCAGCCCGGCCACUCAGACUUGUUUGAAGCUGCACUGGCAGCUUUUUUGUCUCCUUUGGGUAUUCACAACAGCCAGGGACUUGAUUUUGAUGUAUUUUAAACCACAUUAAAUAAAGAGUCUGUUGCCUUA